AGGAGCUGGCCCGCCUCCAUGGUUCAUCAGGGAAGCUGUGGCUCCAGCCUCGCGGGAUACAUACACGCAUACACACACACACACACACACACACACACACACACACACACACACCUACACACCCCACAAACAAUAGUCCAGGCUGGAUCUCUCCUCCUGUCUCUUCUCUUGGUAAAACUUCUCAGAGAACCAAAGAGAGGCAAAAUUUGAGGCCAGCCGGCAGCAGCAGAGAAGCUGAGGGAGACUUGAGGAUGUAGACUGCCCUGCCCUGCUGUGGCUGCUCAACUUUCUUUUUUUUUCCUGAAAAUAUCCAGACACUCUCUUCUCCCAGACUGGGAAGCAGAACGCAGGCCCCCUGCUGUGACGCUGCACCUGAGCAGAGGCUGACCUCAGAGCAGGGCCAGGGGCUAUGUCUCUCAUCUCAUGGCUUCGGUGGAACGAGGCCCCAUCCCGGCUGUCCACCAGGAGCCCUGCUGAGAUGGUGCUGGAGACGCUUAUGAUGGAGCUGACGGGGCAGAUGCGAGAGGCUGAGAGGCAGCAGCGGGAGCGCAGCAAUGCGGUCAGAAAGGUCUGCACCGGUGUGGACUACAGCUGGCUGGCCAGCACACCCCGGUCCACCUAUGACCUCAGCCCCAUUGAGCGGUUGCAGCUGGAAGAUGUCUGCGUUAAGAUCCACCCAUCCUAUUGUGGGCCUGCUAUCCUCAGGUUCCGGCAGCUGCUGGCGGAGCAGGAGCCCGAGGUGCAGGAGGUGUCCCAGCUCUUCCGCUCGGUGCUGCAGGAGGUCCUGGAGAGGAUGAAGCAGGAAGAGGAGGCCCACAAGCUGACGCGCCAGUGGAGCCUGCGGCCCCGCGGCAGCCUGGCCACCUUCAAGACCCGCGCGCGCAUCUCGCCCUUCGCCAGCGACAUCAGGACCAUCUCCGAGGACGUGGAGCGGGACACACCGCCGCCACUGCGGUCCUGGAGCAUGCCCGAAUUCCGGGCGCCCAAAGCCGACUGACCCCGGCCGCUUCCCUGCCCAGAAGCGGAGCCUUCUGCAGGGGGAAUGAUAGGCCGGUGACCGGAGCGCCGGGCCCUGGAACCUCCCCACCUAGGCCUGACGAGGAGACCCAAGAGGCGGCCCCAUCCCAAGACGCUGCUAUAAAAUGAAGCGACUCCCUGCCCCAUCCUCUUCCUCUGGCCACAAAGCUGAGUUAGGUCGUAGAGCGGCACCGCCCUCUCCCUCUCCUGCGCUAGUCUGCAGGAGCAGCCCCUUCCCUAACUGGCAGAUUCAAGGUUUUGGAAGACAGACCAUUGCCCCAUCCUCAUCUCCUGGUUCUGUCUAAAAGGGGACAGUUGCCCUGCCUUUUGGCAAGACCUAGGUUCUCACCCCAAUUUCAGGGAUGUCCCAUUCACCCCCCUACCCCCAUCCCCAAUGAGAAGGGACCUGUUGGCUGGUAUGCCUUCUUGCUAGUGACUGGCUGAGCUCACCACUGCAGGUGGGUCACACACAGCCUCAUAGGCAGGCACAGCUGGAAGGGACCAGAGAGACAUUUAGAUCCACUCUCUUCAGCUAGUAAAUGUGGAACUUGAGGCUCAGAGAGGGACACUUCUUCUGCCUUUAACUGCAGCCAGCUCCUCAUGAACAGUGAGAUUGUUCCUGCAUGAAUAGUGUCUGUUCCUGAGUUUGGAAUCCUGGGCUAUGAAGGGACAGGUCCAAAGGCUACAUCUCUACCUACCUGUGGCCUGAUCCAUCUCUUACCUUGGCAGUGGGAUGAGAAUCUAAGCUGCUCUCCAAGAAGUGUAGCUAGGGGUGGAGGUAGGUUACUCAUUACCCCACGCCACAAUGUCAUCGCAUGGGCUGUGGCCAGUCCCUAACAGCUUCUUCCAGAGGCUCAGCUCCAAGGACUUCAGAUGCUGCCCUAAAGAGCCCAGGUUUCUCAAUUCCAGGGUUCCGCUUUCUGCAGCUGGUCACACCUGCUCUCUGGCUUUCUCCAGAAAGUGAUGCCCAAACCCCUGACUGACCUUGAGGCAGCUGAGUGAAAUGUUCUAGAAGAGCUUCCUGCAGCUUCAUUGUCCUUCCCUUUUCUAACAUGGUUAGGCCUUGAUGAUGGGCAUGUGGAUUACCCAAUGUGUGGAUCACCCAUGGAAAAUCUGGAAGGCCAGGAGGCCUUCCCACACACUCUGGGGUUGAAGUGGGGUGUAAGGGGGAUGGGUGGGGAAGUGUCUACCCUCAACUACCAGCACACAUGCAGAAAAUGCAAGUGGACCUUAAUAGUAGCCUAAAUAAAAUACCCGGAGGAGAUAUAAUCAACAGGGGGGAAAAGUGUGUAUUCCCUCAGUGGAAAAAAGUUUUUUUGAAUGAUUUGGUUUUGAACUUCCCUUUUGAAGUUUUUUUGGAUUUUCACUUGAAUCUGGACAGAGAAUCAUAGGAUGGUGGAAAACCUCUGAUCCAACACUAUCAAGAUGAAAGAGUUGAUUGGCUUAUUAAUGUAAUUGGUAGAAGUUGAGAAUCACUUAAAAUAUACAUCUUAAACAUCUUACGUAUUUUAUUUGAAGACAUAAAAAGUUCACUUGGUUGCCAAACUUUUUUUUUUUUUUUUGAGACUGAGUCUCACUCUGUUACCCAGGCUGCAGUGCAGUGGCGUGAUCUCGGCUCACCACAACCUUUGCCUCCCGGGUUCAAGUGAUUCUUCUGCCUCAGCCUCCUAAGUAGCUGGGACUACAGGCACGUGCCAUCACCCCAGCUAAUUUUUGUAUUUUUAUUAGAGAUGGGGUUUCACUAUGUUGCCCAGAAUGGUCUUGAACUCCUGACCUCGUGAUCCACUCGCCUUGGCCUCCCAAAGUGCUGGGAUUACAGACAUGAGCCACUGUGCCUGGCUGCCAAACUUUUGAUGUGGGUCCAAGCUGUGCUUUUUUGUGACCUAUAUGUUUUGUCUGGUGGGAGUUCUACACUUAAGUUUUCUUGGUUUGCACUUUAAUCAUAACAAUAAGAACAACUGGCGUAAAAGAGUUUUGGAACAAGCAGAAGUGACCCUUGGUAAGCAGACUGCUCAGCUGGUAGGGGCAAAAGUGUUGGGGGAGGAUUAGAAAAAGGCCUCCACAUUGUGGGCUUUCCGGGUGCCCUGGAUGUGGGUCAGCAAAUGUUUUAGAGGAAGUAGUUAACCUGGAGGGAGAUUCAAAGGAGGCUGGAUAAGAGAAUGUCUAUUUUUCUCCUUCCCUAUCACCUUACAUGUACCUAUUCUCCCCAAAGAGAAGGAAGACCUUAGGCUUUCAAUGUGGUGUUCUUUCUUAAGUUUAAGUAACUGGCUGCCAAUGAAAACCUUCCCUUCGAGCCGCAGGCAUGUGGACAGAAUCCACCACCCUCCUUAGACACUCCUCAGACUACUACAGGCUAUCCCCAGCUGGUGGCUCUCAAAUUCAUGAGGGUCCAGAAGUUGUUCCUCUGGAUUCAGGUUGUUAAAGGGACUAAUGAGGUCUGCUUCCAUUACUAUUAUUGAAACCUCAAUAACCACAAAUAAAAGAACAAAAAGUU